AAAAGAUUUCUAUAGGCUCCAGGGAGGUUACGGCCGAGGCGGCGGCGGCGGCGAGCCCGGGGGCGAGGCGCGGACGGGAACAGGAAAAGCCUCCGGCAGCCCCUGCGGGCGGCGGCGCAGCCACGGCCGCGCUCCGAGGUGAAGCCGCGCGCGGAGAGGAAGCGGGUGUUUUCCCCUCUGCCUUUCGGCCCCCGCCCUUCCUUUCAGUUUCUGCCCGCUCGCUCGGAAGUUGGCGGUUGACAAAAAUGGCAGGAGCCGGGGCCCGGGCCGGUUGCCGCAGCGCCGCGGGGACCUUCUGAGUUGGCCCGGUGGCAGGGAGACUCGUGCAGGGGCGUCCGAUGCGCGGGGCCCGGGGCCUCGGGAGAGCUCAGCUGCUGCGGGCCCCAGACGAGGCGACAGGGAUGGACUUGCGUAGACAGCCAGCGCCGGGCCGCCGGGCGCGCGGUCUGGGAGGGCGUGCCGCCGCGGCGCCGGGCCGCGCUCUGUGAACCGGCGAGGCGGGAAGGGGCCGCCGUGGUGCUCGGCACGCCCGGGCGUGUGGCGGGCGGGCGAGAGCUUGAGCGCGAUCCGGGCGGCCGCUGUGCGCAAUCAGUGCAGGCUCCCGCCCGACUCUGACUCGGCGCGGCCGCGACAGUGCCGGCCACACCCUCUGCCCCGCUGCCGCCGGCGCCGCUUCCCAAGAGCUGGAGGCAGGAGAUGCGCCCGGGGCGGCCGCGCGUCCCAGAGAGCCAGCCCCGGCCGCCGUCGCGGGGAAGUGCCGCCUGGUGGGGUCACGGCGCCUGAAGCCCACGUGCGCCGCCGAGCCCGAGGUGGCCUCGAGCGCGGCGGCUGACAGCACAGCCCGCCUGAGCUGCCUCCCGCGCUCCUCCCCGAGGAAAGGAUUUUGAUUUCAAAGAAAGGAAGGAAGGAAGGACAACUCCCAGCUUCCCCGUCCCGCCCUCCCCGCUCCGAGGGCCGCGCCAGGCCAUGCCCAAGAAGGCGGCGGCGGCGGCGAACCAGCAGAAGGGACUUUCCUGGCAGCCCGGCGACGAGGAGCGCGGACAGUGAGUUUGCUCUGCCCCGGUUCAUGGUUCCUGCAAGCCCUCUAGGAGGCCGAAAGCUGCAGCCCCUCCCCUUGCCCCGAAGAGCCUUCCGCGUUCUCUCGCCCUCGGGCCCACCCCGCGCCGCCCGGGCUCCCGCCGCCGCAGCCCAGUGCCCUCUGCCCGCGGCGGUGGAUGGCAUGAUGGUGCGGGGAAGGCACCGCGGCCUUGGCCAGCUGAGUCGCGACGGCCGCCGGGGCGGCGGCAGUGGCCGCGGCAGCGGCGGUGGUAGCGGGCUCCCCAGCGGCAUGCCAGUGCCCCCCGGGCGCGAUGGCUAGCGGCAGCGCCGGGAAGCCCACUGGCGAGGCGGCUUCUCCGGCUCCUGCGAGCGCCAUCGGCGGGGCCAGCUCGCAGCCGCGGAAGAGGCUGGUAUCCGUCUGCGACCACUGCAAGGGCAAGAUGCAGCUGGUGGCUGACCUGCUGCUGCUGUCGAGCGAGGCGCGGCCCGUGCUCUUCGAGGGCCCCGCCUCCUCUGGUGCCGGCGCCGAGUCCUUCGAGCAGUGCCGGGACACCAUCAUCGCGCGCACCAAGGGGCUCUCCAUCCUCACCCACGACGUGCAGAGCCAGCUCAACAUGGGCCGCUUCGGGGAGGCGGGGGACAGCCUGGUGGAGCUGGGCGACCUGGUGGUGUCGCUGACCGAGUGCUCGGCCCACGCGGCCUAUCUGGCCGCUGUGGCCACGCCGGGCGCCCAGCCCGCGCAGCCGGGCCUGGUGGACCGCUACCGCGUGACGCGAUGCCGCCACGAGGUGGAGCAGGGUUGCGCCGUGCUGCGCGCCACGCCGCUGGCCGACAUGACGCCGCAGCUGCUGCUGGAGGUGUCGCAGGGCCUGUCGCGCAACCUCAAGUUCCUGACGGACGCGUGCGCCCUGGCCAGUGACAAGUCACGGGACCGCUUUUCGCGGGAGCAGUUCAAGCUGGGCGUCAAGUGCAUGAGCACCAGCGCGUCGGCGCUGCUGGCCUGCGUGCGCGAGGUGAAGGUGGCGCCCAGUGAGCUGGCGCGCAGCCGCUGUGCGCUCUUCAGCGGGCCCCUGGUGCAGGCAGUGAGCGCCCUGGUAGGCUUCGCCACCGAGCCGCAGUUCCUGGGUCGCGCGGCAGCUGUGAGCGCCGAGGGCAAGGCGGUGCAGACCGCCAUCCUGGGCGGCGCCAUGAGCGUGGUGUCGGCCUGCGUGCUCCUGACCCAGUGCCUCAGGGAUCUGGCGCAGCACCCCGACGGGGGCGCCAAGAUGUCGGACCACAGGGAGAGGCUGAGGAACUCGGCCUGCGCCGUGUCUGAAGGCUGCACCCUGCUAUCUCAGGCUUUAAGGGAGAGGUCUUCGCCCAGGACUUUACCGCCAGUGAAUUCCAAUUCUGUGAAUUAGCACCCCACCCCCAUACCCCUUCUUCCACCCCCAGACUAAAGGAAGAUACUUACUCUCUGCCCCUCUCCAUUUAUACCAAAGAAAUCAUAGGUGAAACCCCCUACCCUCCCCAACGUUAAAUGCUCGAGAGGAAUCUUCCACAAGGCAGGGCCAUGCACGCAACCUGCACACGCACUUGGAGGGCCCAGGUGUCUCUCCACCAGCCCCCAUGCAGUAGGGACUGGAAGAUAUGUCAUCUGCUGGUUGUGUUAUCACUCCCACCCCCUACCCCAGCCCGUCUUCCGGAAUUUCUCAACUAAAUUUCAUUAUUGGGCAGGAAGGAGGUCAUGGGUUCAUUUCAUUUUUGUUUUUUGUGUUUUUAAUUAAAAGAAAGGUUACCUCAGUUUUCACUCCUUAGACAUGGAUGUAGCUACCUUUUUUUGUAUGUCUUUUUUUUUUUUAAGCAAUCGUGUUGAAUUAGGAGUAUACUUGGUGUGGAAAGAGUAUGAAUUUGCCAUGUGAUUUGCAAAUGGGGGGAAGCUACUGUGAGCGUGUGUUUUUUUAAUUUACACUAUAGAGUGAUUUUUUUUUCCCCCAACGUCAAGUUUUUACCUUGCAUGUACUGGAGUAUUUAUUUCAUCUAUUAAAAUGUUAUGUUUCUCAGAUGGCUUUUUGCAAUUAUUGUUGAUUUUUCAAUAAUUGUAAUUUUGCAUGCUGCAUGUCAUGUAUGGGAAGGGUCUGUGGGAAGGCUAUUUCAAUAGUAGUGAGGCGGGCCCCCAAUUCCCAGCCCUUUCUACUAUUUCCUCAAGAAAAAGUACUGCUCAAGAAGUACUCCCUUGAGCAGCCUGGAACUGAAGAGAGGACUAUGUGUAACGUUCUAUUUUAAAAGGCAGGUGACACAAAUGGGAUUGGGUUAUGUAGAGUGCUUGGGACGGUUUUGUCUCAUUUUUCCUGGAAAGUGAUUUAGCUCCCUUUGUCUCCACUUACCUUUCCAUCAUCAUGAACAGUGGCUCAGGCUGCUUGAAUUCUGAUUUGUAUUCUGCCUAUCAUUUUCAGAUUAAAUCCUAAUCCUGUGUGGUAUGCCAGCCUUCCCAACUCAGAGUCUCUGGAUGGAACUCUAAAAGUACUGUACAUCAAGUGAGAAUAGUUAGCAUCUUUUAUGUACACAGGUCUAUUCAGACAAGAUCCUCAUGAUUUCAGAAAAAAUAUAGAGAGGGUCCUAGACUGCUUAAUAGAGGAAAGAAGUAUCCUGGAAAGCUUGUUAAGAACGUUCUAGAGCCACAACAUGAUUGUAGGCCAAGGGCUUGUUUUUGUGACCUUGAUCUAAGAUAAUGCCAUGGUUGAUUGUAUGUUGGAAGAAUCUUUGAUUGGAAUUUGGAGUAAUAUUAAGGUAGUUUGUCUUUUCUGCAGACAUUUUUAGGAGUCUUUUUGUGUGAGUGGUGGUGGAGUGUAUAGUUUUGUUGAACCUAGUUAAAUUCUGAAUAUCUUCCCACUAAAAGCACAACAAAUCUAUUUACAGUGCCUGAAGCCUGGGAGAGCCACAUGAGUAAAAACUCGUACGUGGUUUAGAUUUGUUCCAUUUACAUUUUUCUUGGGAUUUGUUGUGCUUAAACCUUUGCAGUUCCCACAGAUCUGAAAAGAAAGCAUUUUUCACUGUAAUACAUUAAGAGAGAGAGAAAAAAGUCAUAUUGACUAUUUUACUUGUUUGAAUCGCUGUUUUUAUUACAAUGACAUGAAAUACAACGUGUAAAAGUCUUUAACCUGUGUUGGGUAAGGGUAGGACUGUUUCACCACCCUGAAUUUGAAAUUUGAAAAAGUCUUAAAGUGGUAGGGUACUUAAAUUUUUAAAAAAAUGACCAUGGGAGCAGUUUUUCUCUGUUAAAUCCUGGUAAACUUCGGGUUUUUGAAGACUUUAAAAGAUGAAAAUGACCUUGAGCAUCUUUAUUCCUUUCCUCUGCCCCUUAAUGUUGGGAUGGGGUUCAGGAUGAAAGGGAGGUGGGAUUCUAAUUCAUGUGCCAGUGACAAUCCUGCAUGCAUAUAGAAAUUUUUAUUUAUUGAAUGUACACAAGUAAUGAUGGAGUUUGAUUAUAUGGUUCAUUUUCAUUUAUCCUAUGCAGAUCACAAAGAGUAAACUGAAAGGAACAAACGCUAAGUAAAAUAAGGGCCAGAAAUCUGUAAAUUUGGUAUUAGAUUAAGAAAAAAAGAAUUGCCAGUUUUUUCCUGGACUCUUUCCUUGCAGAAGCGAUUUUCAGGACAACUCAAGCCAAUUAAAAAAAAGAAAAUCACUUUCCCUAUCUGUUUGGAUGAAGUUAACUAGCUAGUCACUAAGUGAAUUUUGAAACCUCUUACCUAAAUGAUAGCUGCUCUUGGUGUUUCUUUAUGCUCUACGUUUGGUCAUGUAACAUGCAUAAUCUCUGUUCUCUGAAGUUGAUUAAAGUUCUAAACUUAA